AAUAUGGCAAGAGCUCCUAAAAUCUACUGUCUUAGCAGAAAUCCCCGGUAUAAUUCAAUGUUGUUGACUAGGAGUCCUCAUGCACAUUAGGUCUCUGGGCGAUGCAUCUUGCAUAUCUGCCUCUCUGCGUCCUUUCACCUACAUCUCCCGUUUCCUCCUUCACCUCCCCCACCCCUGCUCCUUGGUAACCACUGUUUUAUUUUCUAUGUCUUCUACUUAAAAAAAUAUAUUCCACCUAUAAGUAAGAUCACAUACAAGCAAGGUCAUGCAGUGUUUGUCUUUCUGUGUCUGGUUUCUUUCACUUAGCAUAACGUCCUCCAGGUUCAUCCGAAUUGUGGCAGAAGGCAGGAUCUCUGUCUUUUUUAAGGCUGAAAAAUAUAUUCAUAUUCUCUCUCUCUCUCUCUCUCUCUCUCUCUCUCUCUCUUUCUCUUUCUGUCUCUCACACUUUCCUUACUCAUUCAUCAGGGAGGUUCUUAACUGAGAGAGUGAAGCCACCUCGUGCUGGUGCAUCACUGAGAGAAAGUAAACCAAACCCAAACCUGAAACGGAUGGUUCAAGUGCCCAGAACCCACUUUCUGGUUGAAUCUUUCUGACUCUCUAAGGGUUAGUAAGGAUUUCUCUGGGGAAAGAGAUAGGGGCUGGGCGUGGUGGAUCACGCCUGUAAUCCCAGCACCUUGGGAGGCUGAGGUGGGCAGAUCACUUGAGGUCAGGAGUUCAAGACCAGCCUGGCCAACGUGGUGAAACCCCAUCUCUACUAAAAAUACAAAAACUAGCUAGGUGUGGUGGCGUGCACCUGUAAUCCCAGCUACUUACUCGGGAGGCUGAGGCAGGAGAAUCACUUGAACCCGGGAGGUGGAGGUUGCAGUGAGCCGAGAUGGCGCCACUGCACUGUAGCCUGGGCGACAGGGCGAGACGCCGUCUCAAAAAAAAACACACAAACAGAAAGUGAUAGGAACCCUUCCAUCACAUCAAGCCUGGUGCUUCUAUAUGAUUGGAAUGACGGUACUGAUGCCCCCCUGGCAGACACCCCUUCUGCCCAUGGGCCUGGCUUUCCAGUCCCUGUUUAAGGAAGACUGCCCCCACCAAGUGCCUCUCCCUCCUGGGGAGCUGGCCCCUUCCACUUCACUUCUGAGACCAUGGCUGGGGCUAAUGAGACUGUCAUUAACAGUGCCUCAAACAAAACCUAAGACCAUUAAAUAUUUAAUUGAAUUAUUUCACUGCAGGGAUAUUGUGACUCAUGUUGAAAACUAAUCACCUGCUUUUUUAUCUGGCCCUUAAUAGAUCUCUGGUUCAACAUUUAAAGGUCAGAGUCAUGGCGAUCGCAGUAUUGUCAUUGUUUUCUUUCCUUUGUGGGUUUGGGUGGAGGAAAGGGGAAGAGUGGGAUGCGUGGGAAGGAAGAGGAGUCAUUGGAAGUUGCCUUUAUCAGUGGAGGGAUUCCAGGGGAUCAUAGGAGCUAUGCUUCUUCUUUUCUGGCCUUCCCUGGUCUUGAUUCCCCAGAGGGAUACCAGGAAGGGGCUGGAAUGUGGGUGCGGAUGACCUCUGAACUAGGCGAUCCUGUUUAAUGCAAGAAACUGUAUUCCCUGUCCAGCCAUUCACGAUACUGUUUCAUUCGCUCUAUCAGAGCUCAGUGAGGCGUUGAAAUUCCAUUGUUCUUCUUUUUAAUUUAAUUUUUUAUGCAGGAAGAUGAAAAGAUGUUUUAAAAUCCUCAUGGUUUUUUCUUCCUCUUCUCAGUGUUAUUACUAUGUUAACAAGAUAGCCAUUCCUGCCACUAACAUCUGUGCUCAGCCUGUGGUCAGGUCCUGACUUGAGUAUUCUAGCAAUAAAAUCGGUGUACUUAAUUAGCUUUUUAGGUGACUCCAGCCUGUGCUGCUGCUUGUACCAUUUGAUGGGAAUUUCAGGAGGAAGGAAUUAAGGCCUGUGGACGUGAAGACAUGUGGCUGACACAGGGUUUAUGUUGGUAAAAGAUCAACUGUGAAAUAUUUGGAGUGUCCAAUGCAUGCCGUGACCUUGCUAGACACCCUUGGGAGUUGUAGAGCCAGUCCGAUGCCCUCCACAAAUACCUUGGAUUUUCUAGAGAGGAGCAAAAGCUAUUUCUCUUAGAAGAUUUUAGUGUAGCAUUUUCCCACAGACAAAAAUGCCCAAGUUUGGGUAUGAAGCCCCAACUGCUAACUUUCUUUGCAUCUGUUGAAGAUGAUGAACAGGAGAAAGUUAAAGCAGUGGAUAGAAAAACAGUUGUGCUGGCUGGGCGCAGUGGCUCAUUCCUGUAAUCCCAGCACUUUGAGAGGCUGAGGCGGGCGGGUCACCUGAGGCUGGGAGUUCUGAGACCAGCCUGACCAAUAUGGAGAAACCCCAUCUCUACUAAAAAUAAAAAAUUAGCCAGGCAUGGUGGCGCAUGCCUGUAAUCUCAGCAACUCAGGAGGCUGAGGUAGGCUUUGAACCCGGGAGGCGGAGGUUGCAGUGAGCCAAGAUCGCGCCAUUGCACUCCAGCCCGGCCAAGAAGAGCAAAACUCUGUCUUCAAAAAGAAAAGAAAAGAAAAGAAAAGAAAAGAAAAACAGUUGUGCUGUAAUUUUUGUACUGUUAUUGCCUGGCUGAAAACCAGGCCUGCCGCUGAUGGCCCUAAAGGGAACCGCAUCUGCCAGGACGACAGAGCGUCAGCAAUGUGUUGGACUCAUCAUAAAGCAGACACAUGUUUCCUGCAUUAUGGAGCUGUUGGGCCACAUGACCUAGAAGCCCUUCUGGUGCCAGGAGUCUGAAUUCCAUGAUGCUUACAUCCAGCCAGCUAGUGAUUGCAGAAAACCUUUAAAAAAAAAAGUCUGAAAAGAUUAACCAGAUCUAUUUUGUGCAGGUUCAUUUGUGUUCCCAUUGGCUUUAAUGACACCUCCUCCCUCCCAAAUUUCACAGUGAUUUGUUCCUUUCCUCUUUAACGUCAUUCAGCGGUAUUUUUUGAGUGCUGCUCUGUGCCAUGCACCGUGCAAGAGAGGGGAGCCCCACCUGCAAGAAGCUUAGUCUUGGCAGAGGAGACAAAAAGUAAAGAGACAAUGGCAGGACGGGUGUGACGGGGCACAGGGGUCUGGUUUAGGCAGAGAGGCGGGUCCCUUGGAGGCAGAGCAUGGGAAAUGCUGCUCAGUCUAGGUGAUACCCAGGCGAGGUCUUAGAGGUGCACAGAAUCCUGUGAGAAGGGCACCAUCCCAGCAGUGGAGUGUACAGAAGCUGGGAGGUGGGACCAGGGAGAUUGGAUCUGCUCUCACCAGGAUGUGCAUGAGGCACAGAAGCAUUGAAGCCAAGCUGAGGCAGUUUUCGAGCGCUUUAAUUGAUUGUCUGAUAAACCCACUUCAAGAACAGAUGGAAGAAUGGAAGAAAGUGGCCAACCAGCUGGAUAAAGACCACGCAAAAGAAUAUAAGAAAGCCCGCCAAGAGAUAAAAAAGAAGUCCUCGGAUACGCUGAAACUGCAGAAGAAAGCAAAAAAAGUGGACACUCUUGGGAGAGGUGAUAUCCAGCCUCAGUUGGACAGUGCUCUCCAAGAUGUCAAUGAUAAGUAUCUCUUAUUGGAAGAAACAGAAAAGCAGGCUGUCCGGAAGGCUUUGAUUGAAGAACGUGGCCGAUUCUGUACCUUCAUCUCUAUGCUGCGGCCAGUGAUUGAAGAAGAAAUCUCAAUGCUAGGGGAAAUAACCCACCUUCAGACCAUCUCGGAAGAUCUAAAAAGCCUGACCAUGGACCCUCACAAACUGCCCUCCUCAAGUGAACAGGUGAUUCUGGACUUGAAAGGUUCUGAUUACAGCUGGUCGUAUCAGACGCCACCCUCUUCCCCCAGCACCACCAUGUCCAGAAAGUCCAGUGUCUGCAGCAGCCUGAACAGUGUCAACAGCAGUGACUCCCGGUCCAGCGGCUCCCACUCGCAUUCCCCCAGCUCACAUUACCGCUACCGCAGCUCCAACCUGGCCCAGCAGGCUCCUGUGAGGCUGUCCAGCGUGUCCUCCCAUGACUCAGGAUUCAUAUCCCAGGAUGCCUUCCAGUCCAAGUCACCAUCCCCCAUGCCGCCAGAGGCCCCCAACCAGUUGUCUAACGGGUUUUCUCACUAUAGUUUAUCAAGUGAGUCCCACGUGGGGCCCACGGGUGCAGGCCUUUUCCCUCAUUGCCUGCCUGCCUCCCGCCUGCUCCCUCGGGUCACCUCUGUCCACCUUCCAGACUACGCUCAUUAUUACACCAUUGGGCCCGGCAUGUUCCCGUCAUCUCAGAUCCCUAGCUGGAAGGACUGGGCUAAGCCUGGGCCCUAUGACCAGCCUCUGGUGAACACCCUGCAGCGCCGCAAAGAGAAGCGAGAACCGGACCCCAACGGGGGAGGACCCACUACCGCCAGCGGCCCACCUGCAGCAGCUGAGGAGGCUCAGAGACCACGGAGCAUGACUGUAUCGGCUGCCACCAGGGUGAUGCUCUUGUUCUCAGUAGCUGGUUGGGGCCACCUCAGCCUGGCUGGGGAUCACAUUCUGGCCAGCAACUGGGGGGCCAAGGCAGCCUUGCAGCUGGAGGGACCUGGGCUCCAUUCCCUGACUUCCUGCUCUACAGCAAAGUCCCUGGGAAAAAAACCUUGUGUGGGAAUGAGAGAGGCAGAACUUUCUAGGGUCAGAGUGGGACCCAAGCAAGUCAAUAGCCCCCUGGCCCCACAGACAUGUAGUGCUCACGGGGGCAGAACAGGAGUGCUGUUGAGCCCCCCCCCUAAAGCAACCUGUGUAUUUCUCUCCUCCAACCUGCAGCCUGGUGAGGAGAUGGAGGCUUGUGAGGAGCUGGCCCUGGCCCUGUCUCGGGGCCUGCAGCUGGACACCCAGAGGAGCAGCCGGGACUCGCUUCAGUGCUCCAGCGGCUACAGCACCCAGACAACCACCCCCUGCUGCUCUGAGGACACCAUCCCUUCCCAAGUUUCAGAUUAUGAUUAUUUCUCUGUAAGUGGUGACCAGGAGGCAGAUCAGCAGGAGUUCGACAAGUCCUCCACCAUUCCAAGAAACAGCGACAUCAGCCAGUCCUACCGACGGAUGUUCCAAGCCAAGCGUCCAGCCUCAACUGCUGGCCUCCCCACCACCCUGGGACCUGCUAUGGUCACUCCAGGGGUUGCAACUAUCCGACGGACCCCUUCCACCAAGCCUUCUGUCCGCCGGGGAACCAUUGGAGCUGGUCCCAUCCCCAUCAAGACACCCGUGAUCCCUGUCAAGACCCCAACCGUCCCAGACCUCCCAGGGGUGUUGCCAGCCCCUCCAGAUGGGCCAGAAGAGCGGGGGGAGCACAGCCCUGAGUCGCCAUCUGUGGGUGAGGGCCCCCAAGGUGUCACCAGCAUGCCCUCCUCAAUGUGGAGCGGCCAAGCUUCCGUUAACCCUCCACUUCCAGGCCCGAAGCCCAGUAUCCCUGAGGAGCACAGACAGGCAAUUCCAGAAAGUGAAGCUGAAGACCAGGAACGGGAACCCCCAAGUGCCACUGUCUCCCCAGGCCAGAUUCCAGAGAGUGACCCUGCAGACCUGAGCCCAAGGGAUACUCCACAAGGAGAAGACAUGCUGAACGCCAUCCGAAGGGGCGUGAAACUGAAGAAGACCACGACAAACGAUCGCUCAGCCCCUCGCUUUUCUUAGGUUCACAAGAAAUGCGCCGGUGGGGAAUGAACUGUUUCAUUAAUAAAACCUAAUUUGUCUUGAUCCAUUCCACUCUAUAAUAAAACAAAAGAUUUUGUAGGCAACUCGGAAUAUAGCUCUUUUGAAAGUACUCGACACCUUUAGAUAAGAAUUAAAACCAACCUAUGUAACUGACAUAAUCUUGAUCUUUUAAUUUGUAAAUAUUGACAAUUUUCUUUCUGCACAUUUUAAUCUUAGUUUCCCUUUUGAUUUUUCUGAAGGUGCCAAAUUCCAUUUAACUUUUUUACAAGUCUUUGUAAAAUUUUAAAUGCAUAAAGGGGGUUGGGGCAGGGGAACCACGAAGUAGUUAAUUUUAGAAAAGGAUUUACUAUACUUCACUCUUCUUUUUUUUUCCCCACAAGCUUUUGUAGAUGCAUUGUAGUAGUCUAGCUUAGAAGCAAAUGCAAGUUAUUUUAAUGUACAAACUAAAUGGGUAAGAGGUAAAAUCUUCAUUUAAAUAUACUAUGUUCUGGAUGAAAAGAGCAGGAGUAACAAUUGAUGAGCAAUAUUCAGAGUGAAGUAAAUCUGGAAAUGGUAGACUGUGUUGGGAUUGGGGGGAGGGCCAUGGGAGGGGUACAUCGUCAACAUAGCCGAUCCUGUUACAUUUAAGAGUAGCCUCGUAGGUUGAAUUUCUUCUGGUAGCUUCAUGGUAAAUGCAUCCGAAUAAGCCAUACUGGAUUGCAGUGUUUGUUUCUGUAGGGUGUUUAAGGACUUGACUUCCUUUCUCCCAUGAUUCCUCUGGACUGCACACAGCACCCACAACCAGCCCCAUGCAUGCUGCUGCCUCUGGGCAGUCGUAGAAUCUCCCACUUCAGUUUCUCGUUGAUUGUACUCACCUUUAUGGAAUCCAAAUACAUCCAAAAGGGUAAGGCAGUUUUAAAAAUGUGAAAACAUUUAAAAAUGAUAAUAGCAGGGAAUUCUUAGAUUAUAGUAAAUGCCUUUUACUUAACUGUGCCCAGCAGGCUGGGUGCGUUAAAAAGCCCAAGUAUUUUGAAAAAACUCGAACAGAUUUGACAAGGGUAGCCAGCUUGGAGUCUAGCAACUUGCCAAUGUGUUUACCAAUCUGGGGGCUUGUUUUUCUUUUCUUCUUUCAAAUAAAUGGCAGUUAACUGGCUUUACAGUAAACAUUGAAGAGAGGAGGAUUUGUUUAUUGUCACUGGGAAUCUGACCACUAUACUGUCCUUUUUUUGUAUUCUGGGUAAAUGUUUUUUGGAAAAGAUUUGUCUUUUCUAAGUGGAAGUUAAAUUUGUUAUACUGCCCAUCCCCUAAAGCCAACAGAGAUUUGUAGAUUUAAAGGGAUCACAUUUGAAGACAAUAGUGUUUAAGAAAGCAAGCAAGUCCCUUAGCAGUCAGGUCAUAACAGGGCACAUUUCUGACCGAACCCUCUCAAGGCAGAGGAGGAGUUUGGUGGGUUUCAUACACCCUGCAGAUUCCUGUUGGCUCUAACCCUCAAUUACCUAAUCUUAUGCUUUAACACAUAACUGCAUUGGAUGUGAGAGUAACGUACCGUAUGGUCAUUGUUCUAUAUAUUAACAUUGAACACUGCUGCGAUUGCUCAAGGACAUUUUAUGUUACGGCUUUAAAGCAAAGGCAUGAUUAUUAGAAACUAUUUAAGCUUUUUUCUUUGAAAAACAAGCUCCUUUUACAGAAUAUAAACAACAGUAGUGCCUGUGGUUUAGCCCACCAAUCUUGAUGACUAAAAGUAGCUGAUGCAUUGUGCAUAUGAUGCUUGAGAUGGUUUUUGCAAAAGCAGAAAUCGCUGCAAGGUAAUCACAAUAGAUAAAAGUGGUAUUUUAAACCUUUGAAAUAAAUGGAUGUAACUGUACCUUGGUACAGCUUUUCACUUGUUUAGUUUUUAAACGUUAGUAUAAUCUGAAUAAAUAAAAUGUUGCCAAAUUCAAUGUAGAAAGAAUGUGACAACACACCUUGGGUAGUUCUGCUUGUGUUUUUGCAUAUUGUAAAAGCAGUGUCACAGCUAAAAAGAAAGAAAUCGUUUCUAACAGUAAAUUAUUGUGCUUUAGUUGCUAGUUUGUACUGAGAGUUGACCUCUCCCUGUGCAGUUUUUUGUUCUAAACUUGUAUAAAUAACAAUUGUGUAAUGUGUCUCCCUCCUACAUUGUAACAAUUGCUUCAGCCUACGUUAUAAAUAAAGAACCACUAGAUUAAAAAA